AUUCCACUUAUCUCCUUCUGGCUAUCCAAUUGCUCAUAGAUGUUUCCACUCUCAUUUUGGUAAGGACGAGAAAUGUUCUCUAAAUAAUUUAGAUAAUCCUAUAAUGUUUGUAUAAUGGAAAGUAUUAGUUUUGAAAUAGCUAUUGAUAUUUGUUUUAUCAAGUUAAUAGAGUUACAUUGCUUUAAAAGCCAAAUGUUAUUAAAGAACAGACCAUUUUCAACUCUUUUUUGCAAUUUUCUGUUUAUUUACCUCUAGCUUCUAAAUAACAUGCCAGUGGUUCAAACUUUUUAUUCUCAGGAUCCCUUUACAAUCUUAAAAAUCAGUGAGGCCCAAAUGAGGUUUUAUGUGAGUUGUAAUAUUUUAUUUAUUAAUCAUAUUAGAAUUUAAAACUGAAAAAGAUUUUAAAUAUUGUUUAUUCAUUUUUAAGUAGUAAUAAUAAACAUGUUAACAAAAAAAAUUUAUAAAAAAUAACUACAUUUUCCAAAAUGAACAAAAAAACCAUUUAGUGAGAAGAGUAGCAUUGUUUUUCAUUGUUCGCAUAUCUCUUUAAUAUCUGGCUUAAUGGAAGACAGCUGGAUCCUCACAUUGGCUUCUGCAUCCAGUUUGUUGUAUUACGUUGUUUGGGUUGAAGUAAAUUUUUAAAAAUCCAACCUUACACAGUUAUGUAGUCAGAAACAGGAGGAGUAUUUUAAUAGUCUUUUCAGGAAAUUGUGGCUAUUCUUAUUUUAUACCAUAUUAAAAUUAACUAGCAGUAGUUUCUGAAAGAUUUGUUGCAAUGUGAAAUCUGAAACCACACCAAUAAACUUUUGUGCUCUGCUAUACUGAAACCUACUGGUCUGUCUUGAACUUUGAAUGGAUAAUAUCACGCAUUGGUCAUCAGGAAAAUUAGUAAUGCAGAUCUUCCAAAAGGUGAUACAUUUUAUUAUAUAAUAUUUUAAAAUCACAUUUGUUAAUAUCAUCACUGAUUUCAUUAAAAAAAUUUAAGUAUUGGAAAACCAUAAACUUACCGUGGAGAAUACAAGUUUUCCAAACUUCUAAUUUUCCCUUGAAACCUCAAAUUUUUUCAUUCCAACAAAUACUGUCAGUUUUUUUUUUACUUGAAAUGUCAGGUUUACUUCCUUCAGUUUUGAGAAAAUGUCUGCUGAAUACCCAAGUUUGAAUAACCAUAAUUUGUCUAUCAUUUGUUCUUUCAAGUUGAAAUAUUGUUUCAUGCAUUAAGCAGCUAGUUCAACCCUUAAUGUAAACAUCACACAAGUGUUCUUCCAUAUGCAACAGAUUUUUAUGCUAUUAGUACUUAUGCUAUUAAUAUUUCUCAUUUUACCACCCAAAUAUUAAGAACACAUGGACUCAAGGUGGAGAUUAAUAAAAGUAAUGAUUUUUACUGCUUCAUCAAGGACAUUUUUUGGUGAAAUGGAAUUUUUCUUUUUCUUUUUUCUUCUUUUUUUUUUUUUGAGAUGGAGUCUCACGUCGUGCAGGCUGGGGUGCAGUGCCGCGAUUUUGGCUCAUUGCAACCUCUGCCUCCUGGGUUCAAGCGAUUCUCCUUCCUCAGUCUCCUGAGUAGCUGGGAAUACAGGUGUGCAUCACCAUGCCCACUAAUUUUUGUAUUUUUAGUAGAGGUGGGUUUUCUCCCUGUUGGUCAGGCUGGUCUUGAACUCCUGACUUCAAGUGAUCCACCCGCCUCAGCCUCCUAAAGUGCUGGGAUUACAGGCAUGAGCCACUGUGCCCGGCCUCUUUUUCUUUCUUGUUUCUUUCUUUCUUUUUUUUUUUUUAAUUGCAAGUGUGGUGGUAAAUGCAAUAACCACUAAUCAGUUUUGCAACAGUGCUUUAAUUUGUGUUGCUAAAGCACCAGCAAUUAGACCCACUGUGGCUUUUGCACCAUCAGUGUAAAUGUCAAUACAAUGAAAAGGCAAAUAAUAUCUUUGUAUUAUAUAAAAAUAGUUCUGUCUUCACAGAAAGUGAACCACACUUUCAGAACCACUGUGAUAUGCUUCUACUGCUAUUGCUUGGUUUGCUGAUGUUAGCCAUUUCUGCUGACUUCCUAUUCUGCAAGAUGAAGGGUUAGCACCCUUUAAACUAGCAUUCCCCUUGCUCCUUUCUUUAUCACUUCAUUAUAAUCAUCACACUGUGGUUUAGGAAACUGCUUACCUUCCAGUUACUACCUAAGUAUUGUUCACUACCAAGCCUGGUAGGGUAAAGUGAAUGCUUCUUUGCUUGUACAACUCUUUAUUUUGAUCUUAAAGUUGAUGACACCAUUUUUUUACAUGCUUAGUUCUGUGUUUCUAUUGCAAAUUUGUCUUAAUCCUCCAACAGAUUUGUGUAACUUCUCCUAAAUAUUCUCUUCCAUGCAGUCUUAGGUGAUCCAUAAGGCCCAUGUUUUUCCCUAGAGAAAUCCCUUUAGAAGCCCUUCUUCCUCCUGCUCCAACAUGGAGCAGCUGCUGGCUCAGUCUGCAACUCAGCCUUCAUUCCGGGACAUUCACUAACGGCUCAGAAGAGGAGAAGUGACCUAGUGGGGAGAUCUAAAAGCUCAUGUUCCAAACUUGUAACCAACCUCCCUGUUUUAAGCUCUGUAUCUCUUCUCCCAUUGUCAGCAAUCUUGUGUCUCCAAAUCCCAAAACUUUCUGGGGUUCUGCUGCACAAAUUGGCUUCUUCUUUGACUAAUAUCCCCAAGUGGGCACUUGGUUUCCACAUUUCUCAAAUCUCCUGGCUCCUCAACCUGCUUUCCACCUUCCGAGAGUUUUGAAGUCUUAGACCUGCUAUUGUCUCCCCUUCCAUUCUUUUUGUCUCUAUGGUUUUGUACCUUUAAAAAAUUCUUUUAUUCUCAUUUUAGGGGCAUUUCAGGAGGGGAGUAAAGAUAAACAUAUGUGCUCCAUAUGUCUUGUUUAAUCGGACAUCCAGUAUUUGAAUUUGGAACUGCACACGCUCUGAGGAUUUGUUUGUACAAGCUCCUUGUGGUCUUGGUAGUUUUAUGCUUUGGGAGAUUUAUGAACCCAUUUCAGCAGCUCUAUGUUCUGCUGCUGCCACAACAGAAAUCAAAGGUUGCCAUAGAACUUGAUGAAGCAAAUAACAAAUACUUAGAAAAUAUUAACUGUGAAUUUUUUCCAUCAUUCAAUCUUUCAACAAACCCAUCAAACACUUAUUUUCUGAGUACCUACCAUGUGCCAGGGCACUAUUGUAGGUGCUGACAUUGUAGUGGUGAAUAAGACCAAUACGGUCCUCUCGUGCACUUUGCAGUCUAGUGAAGGGAGCAAACCACAAUAAAAUAAACAAGUAUAUAAGACAAUUUCAGAUAGUAACAAAUGCUAUGAAGAUAACAAAAGAGGGUAAUGUGCUGGAAUGACUGAGGAUAAGGGGGCUAUAUUGGGAAGAGGGUCAGGGAGGGCCUCUCUGAGAAGGCGACAUUUGAGCUGAGGUCUGACUCAUGAGAAGGACCUAUCUUUGUAAAGGUCUGGGGGAGGAGGGUUUCAGGCAGUGCCAAAAUUCCAAAGUGGGGAAAAGCUUAUGUGUUCACAGAAUCAAAAGACCAACGUGGUUGGAACAUAUUGAAGGGAAGAGUGAUGGGAGAUGGGGUCCAGAAAUCAGAUCUGGAAAGGCAAAUAUGGAUGAUGGCCCAAAUAGAGGUAAUAAUUGAAACUAUAGGAUGAGAUAAGAUGGCCAGAGGAGAGAGAGUAUAUAGAAAACUGUGGUAGGCACUGUGGAUGCUUGCAAGAGCAUCCAAGACACUGUCCUUACCUUCAAAACAUUUACAACCUAGGAAACUGGUGAGGCAAGACACAUUUUCAAAAUAGAAAAUAGUAAAAGCGUGUAUAAUCAGGUAUUUGCAUGACAUAGUAUAGGUUUUUUUUUUUUAGGUGAAGUUAGAAAAUGUAACAAUCAUUCAGAAUUGAUGGUAAAAUAUAGCUUUGUGGAGGAGGUAAUAUCUGAGCCAAAUUUUGAUGGAUGACUUAUAUUUGUAGUAGCUGAAAGGCAGAAAAAGAGAAUCUCAGACAGAAAAAACAUGGGCAGAGACUUGAAUGUGUGGAGGUGACCAUGACAUAUUUAUGGAAUAAUGAAGAAUAGCUUGACUGUUGGGAAGUAAACAGGUGGUACUGUGAAGGCAAGGAGCUUGAAAAUUCCCCAGAUAUUCACAUCGUCCAGGCAGGAAAUCUGCACUCACUGACCAUUGCGGAAGCCUUUGAAGAGGACACAGGACGCUAUUCCUGCUUUGCUUCUAACAUCUAUGGGACAGAUUCGACUUCUGCUGAGAUUUAUAUAGAAGGGGUUUCUUCUUCUGACUCAGAAGGCGACCCUAACAAGGAAGAGAUGAAUCGAAUCCAGAAGCCAAAUGAGGUGUCAUCUCCUCCCACUACCUCUGCAGUCAUUCCUCCAGCAGUACCCCAAGCCCAGCAUUUGGUGGCCCAACCUCGUGUGGCAACCAUCCAGCAGUGUCAGAGCCCCACCAAUUACUUGCAGGGAUUGGAUGGAAAACCUAUCAUUGCAGCUCCUGUGUUUACAAAGAUGCUACAAAAUUUGUCAGCUUCUGAGGGUCAGCUGGUUGUCUUUGAAUGCAGAGUAAAAGGAGCUCCAUCUCCUAAGGUUGAGUGGUAUAGAGAAGGGACUUUAAUAGAAGAUUCUCCAGAUUUUAGGAUUUUACAGAAAAAACCUCGAUCCAUGGCAGAGCCAGAGGAGAUUUGCACCUUGGUCAUUGCUGAGGUGUUUGCAGAAGAUUCUGGGUGCUUCACAUGUACUGCAAGCAACAAAUACGGCACAGUGUCAAGCAUUGCACAGCUGCACGUGAGAGGAAAUGAGGACCUCAGCAACAACGGGUCUCUUCACUCAGCCAACUCUACCACCAACCUGGCAGCUAUUGAGCCACAGCCCUCCCCACCCCACUCAGAGCCUCCAUCUGUGGAACAACCCCCCAAACCCAAACUCGAGGGGGUUCUGGUGAACCACAAUGAGCCCCGGUCCAGCUCCAGGAUUGGGCUUCGUGUGCACUUCAACCUGCCUGAAGAUGACAAAGGAAGUGAAGCAUCCUCCGAGGCUGGUGUGGUGACCACCAGACAGACCAGGCCCGAUUCUUUCCAGGAGAGGUUCAACGGACAGGCAACAAAAACCCCAGAGCCUUCUUCCCCCGUGAAAGAGCCCCCUCCAGUUCUGGCCAAACCCAAACUUGAUUCCACUCAGUUACAACAGCUUCAUAACCAAGUCUUACUGGAACAACACCAAUUGCAAAACCCACCUCCUUCAUCUCCUAAGGAGUUUCCUUUCAGCAUGACUGUUUUGAACUCCAAUGCUCCCCCAGCGGUGACAACAUCCAGUAAGCAGGUGAAGGCUCCUUCAUCACAGACGUUCAGCUUGGCCCGGCCGAAGUAUUUCUUCCCCUCCACGAACACCACCGCAGCAACUGUGGCCCCUUCCAGCUCUCCGGUGUUCACUUUGAGCAGCACUCCUCAAACUAUUCAGAGGACAGUGAGCAAAGAAAGCCUCUUAGUGUCUCACCCCUCUGUGCAAACCAAAUCUCCAGGAGGGCUUUCCAUCCAAAAUGAGCCACUCCCACCAGGCCCAACAGAACCAACACCACCACCAUUCACAUUUUCCAUCCCCAGCGGAAACCAGUUUCAGCCCCGCUGUGUGUCCCCAAUUCCUGUCUCUCCUACCAGCCGGAUUCAGAACCCAGUGGCUUUCCUCAGCUCUGUUCUGCCUUCUCUCCCUGCCAUCCCACCCACAAAUGCCAUGGGGCUGCCUAGAAGUGCACCAUCCAUGCCAUCCCAGGGAUUAGCGAAGAAAAAUACAAAGUCUCCUCAACCAGUGAAUGAUGAUAACAUUCGUGAAACUAAGAACGCAGUGAUUCGAGACUUGGGGAAAAAAAUAACUUUCAGUGAUGUCAGACCAAACCAGCAGGAGUACAAAAUUUCAAGCUUUGAGCAGAGGCUGAUGAAUGAAAUAGAGUUUCGCUUGGAACGUACUCCUGUUGAUGAAUCAGAUGAUGAAAUUCAACAUGAUGAGAUCCCCACGGGCAAGUGUAUUGCUCCCAUCUUUGACAAGAGACUCAAGCACUUCCGGGUCACAGAAGGCUCUCCAGUUACAUUCACCUGCAAAAUUGUUGGGAUACCUGUUCCAAAGGUUUACUGGUUCAAAGAUGGGAAGCAGAUUUCUAAGAGAAAUGAGCACUGCAAAAUGAGGCGAGAAGGAGAUGGGACAUGCUCUCUGCACAUUGAAUCCACUACCAGUGAUGACGAUGGCAACUACACCAUCAUGGCAGCCAACCCCCAGGGGAGAAUCAGCUGUUCUGGCCACUUGAUGGUACAAAGUUUGCCCAUUCGCAGUCGGCUAACCUCUGCUGGUCAGUCUCACAGGGGAAGAUCCCGAGUGCAAGAAAGAGACAAAGAGCCCCUACAGGAACGCUUUUUCCGACCACAUUUCCUGCAGGCUCCUGGGGAUAUGGUAGCUCAUGAGGGGCGCCUCUGUCGGCUGGACUGUAAGGUGAGUGGUUUACCGCCCCCGGAGCUGACAUGGCUACUCAAUGGCCAACCUGUGCUACCAGAUGCCUCCCACAAGAUGCUGGUCAGGGAGACCGGAGUCCACUCUCUGCUCAUUGACCCACUCACUCAGCGCGACGCAGGGACCUAUAAGUGCAUCGCUACCAACAAAACCGGGCAGAAUUCUUUUAGUCUGGAGCUCUCUGUAGUAGCCAAAGAGGUGAAGAAAGCACCUGUGAUCCUGGAGAAACUACAGAACUGCGGUGUUCCCGAAGGCCACCCCGUGAGACUGGAGUGCCGCGUGAUAGGCAUGCCCCCACCUGUGUUCUACUGGAAGAAAGACAAUGAGACCAUCCCUUGCACCAGAGAGAGGAUCAGUAUGCACCAGGACACAACAGGGUAUGCCUGCCUUCUCAUUCAGCCAGCCAAGAAAUCAGACGCUGGAUGGUACACGUUGUCAGCCAAGAAUGAAGCCGGCAUCGUGUCGUGCACUGCCAGGCUGGAUAUAUACGCUCAGUGGCACCAUCAGAUCCCACCGCCCAUGUCUGUCCGGCCCAGUGGCAGUCGCUACGGAUCUCUCACCAGUAAAGGACUUGACAUAUUUUCUGCCUUUUCCUCCAUGGAAAGCACGAUGGUGUAUUCAUGCUCUUCUCGGAGUGUAGUGGAGAGUGAUGAACUUUAAGAAUGUCUAGGUACCUGCUGUGUAAGAGAGCGGACUGUGGAGGGGGAAUGAGAACAAGCCAGACUUGGUGGUUUCCAAGCAACCGAAGUUGAGUAAGUUCCCACACUGCUGGACCUGUGGCAAAGAGUGCUUUGAAUAAGUCAGCUAGGGAUUCUUGCAGUCUCAGCUGAGGGAGAAAGGUAGGGCUGUGCCUUCUAAAGAUUCCAACAGAGAUGUGAGAAGAUAAUACAGAUGAACCAAAGAUGUCACACAGUUGCCAUCCACUGCUUUGGGAAAAAACUAGCAUGCUCCCCUGCUCCCUGUUGUGUUAGGGAUGUUUAGGUCAUACUAGGAGCAAUUAGGAGCCAUAUGCCUGGGCUGAGAAGAGCUAGGCAGUAGUGACCUUAGGAUAUGACUAACUCACCAAACAAUGCCAAGGAGAAAGGCGGACAGGUCACCAUCACCUUUCAUCGAUUACAUGUAUAGCAGUAGUUUUGGUGAAUUCACCAAAUCAGCUUCCACUUAGCAUUAGGAGGUCAUGCCAUACAACUCACGUAUGCGGGCAAACACUUUUGAUUUGCAUAUCCUGGGUGUACUGAGCCACAUAAUAAGGUGUCAAAAUGUGCUUGAGAUUCCAAAAACUUGCUGAAACACUUGAUAUUGCACAGUGCACUUAUUUUGUGGCCAAAGCAUGGCCUUACCAGCUUGUCUGCACUAUUUUCUUUUGGGUGGUGACUGUUUUUUUCUGACUUUGCAUAUCCCUAGACACUAGAACUAAAGGAUUGGUAAUAAACCAAUCAGAAAGAAAUCCUCUGUGGGGUCACUUUAAAAACUACUAGCUUCAACUACCACUUACAAAAUGUGCAAGAGUCAUCAUUUGCCCAUAAAAUACACCUCAUGGGCUCCUACCCCUUUCCCCAAAAGUCUGAAAGUGUAGGAGGAAGGAAGAGAUACAAACAAGGAGAGGAAAUGAUGGGAGAGUGUUGUUUUUGUCACUUGCCCCAGCAGAGCAGGGGUUUUGGAAGGAGAGGUCUUUAAUAGCUUUGAAAUGCUUUGAGAUCAUUGGUCAAAUUGCAUUUUCUAUGUAGAGAAUAUUCUGCUAGGUGGAAAAGUUGGGAGAAAGGGGAAUAUGCAUCUUUAUUCUAAUCACCAAUUCAAACCCUGCCUCUUAAGGAAUUUUUAGACUUAAGUUCACUGUGAUAUCCCUAGUACCUAGAAGAGUACCUAGCACAAAGUAGACAUUCAAUAAAUAUUUGCUGGUUGAAUGAAUCUUCUGUUAUUAUGUCUAUUAUAAGAUAACCUAAUCUUAUAUUCUGCAGGAAUAUGCCACCCACACACCAGUCCAAACACUGCCCUGGGAAUGCUCAUCACAGCACAGUUUGCUCUAGGCUGUGCAGGGAAAUGAAUUGCAGGUGUCUGUUUUCAAUUCCCUGUGCUGGAAUCCCUGGUGCUGUCUGUGCCAAGCACACUCAGCUGGCAUUGUAUUUGUGUGAACAGACAGUAACUGCUUAGAAAGGCUUGAAACUGUCUUCACUUCAAGGCAAGGAUUUCCAGCAUAAAAAUAAAUUCAUUCACUGGAGAAA